AAUUCUGUCACACGUGCCCUGGCCUCUGGAGCUCAGCUGCCAGUCCACGUCUAGGGAAUCUUAGCAUCUGGGACCAAGACACUUUACAGCAAUCAUCACCCUUUGCAGAGGAGGUGAGCUCACCAGGACUCAUCUGCCAUUUCAGACCUUUUGCUGCUACCUGCCAGGUGGCCCCCACUGCUGACGAGAGAUGGUGGACCUCUCAGUCUCCCCAGACUCCUUGAAGCCAGUAUCGCUGACCAGCAGUCUUGUCUUCCUCAUGCACCUCCUCCUCCUUCAGCCUGGGGAGCCGAGCUCAGAGGUCAAGGUGCUAGGCCCUGAGUAUCCCAUCCUGGCCCUCGUCGGGGAGGAGGUGGAGUUCCCGUGCCACCUAUGGCCACAGCUGGAUGCCCAGCAAAUGGAGAUCCGCUGGUUCCGGAGUCAGACCUUCAAUGUGGUACACCUGUACCAGGAGCAGCAGGAGCUCCCUGGCAGGCAGAUGCCGGCGUUCCGGAACAGGACCAAGUUGGUCAAGGACGACAUCGCCUAUGGCAGCGUGGUCCUGCAGCUUCACAGCAUCAUCCCCUCUGACAAGGGCACAUAUGGCUGCCGCUUCCACUCCGACAACUUCUCUGGCGAAGCUCUCUGGGAACUGGAGGUAGCAGGGCUGGGCUCAGACCCUCACCUCUCCCUUGAGGGCUUCAAGGAAGGAGGCAUUCAGCUGAGGCUCAGAUCCAGUGGCUGGUACCCCAAGCCUAAGGUUCAGUGGAGAGACCACCAGGGACAGUGCCUGCCUCCAGAGUUUGAAGCCAUCGUCUGGGAUGCCCAGGACCUGUUCAGUCUGGAAACAUCUGUGGUUGUCCGAGCGGGAGCCCUCAGCAAUGUGUCCGUCUCCAUCCAGAAUCUCCUCUUGAGCCAGAAGAAAGAGUUGGUGGUCCAGAUAGCAGACGUGUUCGUACCCGGAGCCUCUGCGUGGAAGAGCGCGUUCGUCGCGACCCUGCCGCUGCUGUUGGUCCUCGCGGCGCUGGCGCUGGGCGUCCUCCGGAAGCAGCGGAGAAGCCGAGAAAAGCUGAGGAAGCAGGCGGAGAAGAGACAAGAGAAACUCACUGCAGAGCUGGAAAAGCUUCAGACAGAGCUUGACUGGAGACGGGCUGAAGGCCAGGCUGAGUGGAGAGCAGCCCAAAAAUAUGCAGAGAAACGAGAGGUUUGUCCGCCUUGGGGAAGACACGGACGGGGCCCAGACCGUCCCGGGCGGGCACUAACGCUGUGGCUCUGCGCAGUGGAUGUGACGCUGGACCCGGCCUCGGCGCACCCCAGCCUGGAGGUGUCGGAGGAUGGCAAGAGCGUGUCUUCCCGCGGGGCGCCGCCAGGCCCGGCGCCUGGCCACCCGCAGCGGUUCUCGGAGCAGACGUGCGCGCUGAGCCUGGAGCGGUUCUCCGCCGGCCGCCACUACUGGGAGGUGCACGUGGGCCGCCGCAGCCGCUGGUUCCUGGGCGCCUGCCUGGCCGCGGUGCCGCGCGCGGGGCCUGCGCGCCUGAGCCCUGCGGCCGGCUACUGGGUGCUGGGGCUGUGGAACGGCUGCGAGUACUUCGUCCUGGCCCCGCACCGCGUCGCGCUCACCCUGCGCGUGCCCCCGCGGCGCCUGGGCGUCUUCCUGGACUACGAGGCCGGAGAGCUGUCCUUCUUCAACGUGUCCGACGGCUCCCACAUCUUCACCUUCCACGACACCUUCUCGGGCGCGCUCUGUGCGUACUUCAGGCCCAGGGCCCACGACGGCGGCGAACAUCCGGAUCCCCUGACCAUCUGCCCGCUGCCGGUUAGAGGGACGGGCGUCCCCGAAGAGAACGACAGUGACACCUGGCUACAGCCCUAUGAGCCCGCGGACCCCGCCCUGGACUGGUGGUGAGGCGCCCUCGUGGCCGCGGGACUGGCCCCGGGGGGCCCCCUGGAUCCCAGGCCAGCGCUUUGCUCUCCUGCUCCGUCUGAAGGGAGCAGGUGCACCAGCCAAAAUGUCAGCGAGGGGGACAAAGAGAGGGACCUUUGCCUACGUAGAUGUGUAUGUGUAGUGCGAUUUUCUUCAAGGAAAGGAGACAAGUCCAAAGCUCGUUUGUGGAUUGUGGGACUGAGCGAAGGAGUACAAAUAUAUCCACGUCGCUCAGAGCUGGGGUGCUCACGGUGGGCGGUGGGCAAGAAGCCAGCAUGGAAGAAAGAAGGGAGAAAACUUUGGUGACUGCCUUAGAGGGAUCAGUUAAUUUGUAUAGUUUUAUAUUUUUUGUAUAUGUUUGCUAGCUCUAAAAAGGUCGAGAUGCAAUAACACUUCGUAAGCAACGAGUUCACCUAAGUAAGGCUCAGAUCCUAGUUUUAAAAACCAUUUCCCAUUAAAAUGAAGUUGGAGGAACAGCUGCUUCUGGAGCCGGGGCAAAAAUUUCAAGGUGAGCCUGGAGCAUUGUGUGUGGUGAAGUAAAAUAAAGGCUCAAAACGUGACGGCAACCCGGCAAAAGGGUAGGGAGCCAGGCCGAAGGGGCCUCACUGACCAAUUGUGGGACAAUUUGAACAUCAGGAUGAAUAAUGACAGGAGAGAUUAUAACACACUGAAUAAAAACAUAAUCCAUGAGUUCAUGCUGAUACUCAAAUUUCUUUUUAAAAAGGAGAAACAGGAAGGUUUCUUUUGGAGGUGAAAUCUAAUUAUUGGUGAGAGUCUUGGAGAACAGGCUGUUUCCAGUCUCAAAGCAGUAACCUUAUACACUACUUAUAAGUUUGAAAGGGGAAAGGUUACCUUUACAAUGGAGACAUCUACCAGAUCAUCCAAGUGAUUAAAUUUAACAUCAUCAAUGAUGGGACCAAGGACAUUAUUAGUUUGACAACUGGGGAAAGAAGUGUUCUUCACCCCCUACCCCCAAGACAUUGUCUCUGUCGGCCAGGCUGGAGUGCAGCCUCAACCUCCUGGGUCCAAGUGAUCCUCCCACCUCAGCACACAACACCAUGCCCAAUUUUAAGUGCGUUAUAGAGACGGGGGUCUCACUUUGUUACCCAGGCUGGUCUCAAACUCCUGCGCUCAAGCAAUCCUCCCACCUGGGCCUCCCAAAAUGCUGGGUGUACAGGCAUGAGCCGCUGUGCCUGGCUUCAUUUUCAGAGUGAGACAUUUGUACUGUGGCUAUGUAGGAGAACAUUCUUGUUCUUAGCAAACAUACUGAAGUUUUUAGAUAUUAAUUACCACAGUGUCUGCCACUGAAUUUCCAGUGACUAAGUGGAAAAAUAUAAAACAUAUGAAUAUAAAGAAAGAAAGAGACAAGUCAAAUGUAGUAAAAUGACAACACUUGGUGACUCUAGGUGACUGGUCGACAGAUGUUCAUUGUACUAUCAAUGUGGCUUUGCUGUGGGUUUGAAAUUUUGCAAACUAAGAGUUGGGUGGCGGGGAGAAGGAUACACCAAAAAACUAAGUGAUUAUCUUUGGAUGGGAAAAUGUUUGGUAAUUGCAUUCUUAAAAUGUCUUCUUUGUAUUUUUUAAUGUUCAAUAAUGUAUAUGUAUCAGUUCUGUAAUAAAGGGGAAAACACUUUUUUUAAA